UGCCGGUCAUGUACCAGGCGUCCAUUGGCCUCUGAGCCAGUGGACGAGCGCAGUCCUCUUUGGGAGUUGUAGUCCCCUAUUGUUGUCCAUGCUGCAAAAUGAAGUGACGAAUGGGUGGGUACCGGUUUGGUUUUCAUGGGGUUUUUGUUUUGUAAAUGAAAAACGACCUUGCGCAAGAUUCCUUUCCUCUAUGCCUGAGGUUUUUGUACAAAAAGUGAGCAGUUCUUGGGGGUACAGGAAUUGAGAAGUCUGGGGUUCCAGAAGUUGGGUGGUGGGGAAGACACGCCCUGAAAGCUCCCAGCUGCAGUACCUCUAGGGGAGAAAGGAUUGCUUAGUUCAGCGAAAAAUGGGGAGAAGUCUGGCACCGUGCUCUGCCUCCCCUGGCCUUUGGUGACCCAAGGCAUGAACUUCAGUAAGCUUCUGCUCCCUCAAAUACUUCAAGAAGGGAAUCGCCCUCUUGCUAUUUCCUUGGAAAUUUUCGAGCCAUUGUUUUGAAAGAGAAACAAAAUUGCAGCAAGGGCUUUUCAGGAUAGCGAUGUUGUCUGGAGAGUAUGUUCAAAGAAUAAAAUAGUUUAGAGAAACCGACAUCGGGGAUUUGUGAAACUAGAAGUCUCCUACGUGGGUAGGAGAUCUGGACCUUAGGGCAGACUUUGAAGACACCUUGGUCUUCUUGUCAAACAGGGAACUAUGGAAUGAGAUGCCUGAUAGAUUUUCAGUUUUUUCAGCCUGCCUCUUUAGACAUGUUAAUGAAGUCAGUGGUUUUUCAAUUCGCUGAUUUCACUGACCAGGUGGCCGCCACUGCAACUCUGCAAGAGACCCAGUAUUGAAAAACGAGAGAGGGGUAAUUGAUGGGGGAAAAAUUGAGUGGGUUCAAGACGGAGUCCAUCUGCUUCUUCCCAUAGAUUUAUUAUUCACUUAUUUGAUAGUUACUAUGUAUCCACCAAAUUAGGAGCUAUGGUUACAAAAUGAUUAAGAAUUAGCUCCCUGUCCUCCAGGAUGUUGCAGUCUGGUGAGAAGCAUACAAUCAAUAAAAUGUGGUAACCACUCAGAAAUGUAGUAUCAAGUCAACGUCAUUGUUAAUUCACAUUCGAUCACACAGAUCAAUGUAUUUCUUUUUUUUUUUUUUGUAUUUUUAGUAGAGACAGGGUUUCACUGUGUUAGCCAGGAUGGUCUCGAUCUCCUCACCUCGUGAUUCGCCCGCCUUUGCCUCCCAAAGUGCUGGGAUUACAGGCGUGAGCCACCGCGCUGGGCAGAUCAAUGUAUUUCUAAGUUGCCUUCUAAAUGAGGGAACAUCAACUUGUGUAAGCCCUCUCUACCCACUUAAAAUAUAAUGCUUUACGUUUUAGGGAAAUGAACACAGUCAUUUUGUGGGAGUAGAAAUAACUCAAAAUACACAAUCAGAUAACUUGUUUCAAUUUGUCUCUAUAUUAGCUGUAGGAUCCUAGGAAAGUCCUUUAACUUUGCAGGGCUCCAGCUCCUCGUUUGUAAAAUCUGCUUAUUUGACUGUUGUGCACAGAAUUGAGAUAACCAACAGAAAGGACUUUAUGAAUUAUGCAAGUGUUAUAGUUACCAUUUUCUUCAUGUCUUAUUGUGAGAUAAAAUAGGCCGGGCGCAGUGGCUUACGCCUGUAAUCCCAGCACAUUGGGAGGCCCAGGCGGGAGAAUCACCUGAGGUCCGGAGUUUGAGACCAGACUGACCAACAUGGAGAAACCCCGUCUCUACUAAAAAUACAAAAUUAGCCGGGCGUGGUAGCGCAUGCCUGUAAUCCCAGCUACUCGGGAGGCUGAGACAGGAGAAUUGCUUGAACCCAGAAGGCGGAGGUUGCGGUGAGUCGAGAUCGCGCCAUUGCACUCCAGCCUAGGCAACAAGAGCGAAAGUCCGUCUCAAAAAAUAAAAUAUAGAUGGCCGCAUGCGGUGGUUUACGCCUGUAAUCCCACCACUUUGAGAGGCCGAGGCGGGCGGAUCACCUGAGGUCAGAAGUUCGAGACCAGCCUGACCAACAUGGAGAAACCACGUCUCUACUAAAAAUACAAAAAUAAGCUGGGCGUGGUGGCGCAUGCCUGUAAUCCCAGCUACUUGGGAGGUUGAGGCAGGAGAAUCGCUUGAACCUGGGAGGCAGAGGUUGCGGUGAGUCGAGAUCGCGCCAUUGCACUCCAGCCUGGGCAACAAGAGCAAAACUCCAUCUCAAAAAAUAGAUAAAUUAGUUAAUUAAAAAAUAAAAAUAAAUGAUUUUAUGAUCCUUCCCUCGCCCCUCGAAAGGUGGGGACAGCCUUUAAGACAGAGAGCAAACCAGUUUUCUCUGUUCGACUACAGAUCUUUAGGAUCUUGGAUUUAAGAAAAUGACCUCAAAAUGUCCGUCAGAGACGUAUUCCCAGGAAGAAAGAUAUUACUUCUACUACAAACCAAAUCAAAAGGAAAUGAAAUUCCAAUGCAACAGGAGUGAACUGCCACGCCUACGGGCUGUUCUCCAAACUGCAGCCUCCAGCCACGACUGCAACGCGCAACCCACUUUCAUUUCUCAUGAGUCAGCGGACACCAUGUCUAGGAGGACCGAGGAAAGGCGCUCUGGCCUUACCAGACACGUCGGACGUCUAUGACACAGCCCCUCUAUCCGUUGCCGGCAGCUGGCGCCAGACUCUCUGGUCGCGGUUUGGAACUGCGCGGGAAGUGGGUGGUGGGCGGGCAAGCGGUAGUGGGUUGUCCCUUGGAGCUGCCCAAUCGACGUGCAUUAUUCUGUUGGCGCACGGCGGCCUUCAAUUACCGUCUCAUUAACUGAUCUCAGCAGCCUGGGAGACACCACCUAUUUGAACUCUAAGGGGGCGGGGCUUUGGGUGUGCCUCCGCUCGACUGGCUGCGGUUGUGAAAGACAGCGGCAGAAGCCAAUCAGCAAAUAAGCUCUUUUUCGGCACACGCAGUCGCUCCACCCGGGUCGCGACCGUUACUGGUGGCGCGCGCGGGGACUUAAAAUCAUGGAGGACACCCAGGCUAUUGACUGGGAUGUUGAAGAAGAGGAGGAGACAGAGCAAUCCAGUGAAUCCUUGAGGUGUAACGUGGAGCCAGUAGGGCGGCUACAUAUCUUUAGUGGUGCCCAUGGACCAGAAAAAGAUUUCCCACUACACCUCGGGAAGAAUGUGGUAGGCCGAAUGCCUGACUGCUCUGUGGCCCUGCCCUUUCCAUCUAUCUCCAAACAACAUGCAGAGAUUGAAAUCUUAGCCUGGGACAAGGCACCUAUCCUCCGAGACUGUGGGAGCCUUAAUGGUACUCAAAUCCUGAGACCUCCUAAGGUUUUGAGCCCUGGGGUGAGUCACCGUCUGAGGGACCAGGAAUUGAUUCUCUUUGCUGACUUGCUCUGCCAGUACCAUCGCCUGGAUGUCUCUCUGCCCUUUGUCUCCCGGGGCCCUCUGACAGUAGAAGAGACACCCAGAGUACAGGGAGAAACUCAACCCCAGAGGCUUCUGUUGGCUGAGGACUCGGAGGAGGAAGUAGAUUUUCUUUCUGAAAGGCGUAUGGUAAAAAAAUCAAGGACCACAUCUUCCUCUGUGAUAGUUCCAGAGAGUGAUGAAGAGGGGCAUUCCCCGGUCCUGGGCGGCCUUGGGCCGCCUUUUGCCUUCAAUUUGAACAGUGACACAGAUGUGGAAGAAGGUCAGCAACCAGCCACAGAGGAGGCCUCCUCAGCUGCCAGAAGAGGUGCCACUGUAGAGGCAAAGCAGUCUGAAGCUGAAGUUGUAACUGAAAUCCAGCUUGAAAAGGAUCAGCCUUUAGUGAAGGAGAGGGACAAUGAUACAAAAGUCAAGAGGGGUGCAGGGAAUGGGGUGGUUCCAGCUGGGGUGAUUCUGGAGAGGAGCCAACCUCCUGGAGAGGACAGUGACACAGAUGUGGAUGAUGACAGCAGGCCUCCUGGAAGGCCAGCUGAGGUCCAUUUGGAAAGGGCUCAGCCUUUUGGCUUCAUCGACAGCGACACUGAUGCGGAAGAAGAGAGGAUCCCAGCAACCCCAGUUGUCAUUCCUAUGAAGAAGAGGAAGAUCUUCCAUGGAGUAGGUACAAGGGGUCCUGGAGCACCAGGCCUGGCCCAUCUGCAGGAGAGCCAGGCUGGUAGUGAUACAGAUGUGGAAGAAGGCAAGGCCCCACAGGCUGUCCCUCUGGAGAAAAGCCAAGCUUCCAUGGUUAUCAACAGCGAUACAGAUGACGAGGAAGAAGUCUCAGCAGCGCUGACUUUGGCACAUCUGAAAGAGAGCCAGCCUGCUAUAUGGAACAGAGAUGCAGAAGAGGACAUGCCCCAACGUGUGGUCCUUCUGCAGCGAAGCCAAACCACCACUGAGAGAGACAGUGACACAGACGUGGAGGAGGAAGAGCUCCCAGUGGAAAAUAGAGAAGCUGUCCUCAAGGAUCACACAAAGAUUAGAGCCCUUGUUAGAGCACAUUCAGAAAAGGACCAACCUCCUUUUGGGGACAGUGAUGACAGUGUGGAAGCAGAUAAGAGCUCACCUGGGAUCCACCUGGAGAGAAGCCAAGCCUCCACCACAGUGGACAUCAACACACAAGUGGAGAAGGAAGUCCCGCCAGGGUCAGCCAUUAUACAUAUAAAGAAGCAUCAGGUGUCUGUGGAGGGGACAAAUCAAACAGAUGUGAAAGCAGUUGGGGGACCAGCAAAGCUGCUUGUGGUAUCUCUAGAGGAAGCCUGGCCUCUGCAUGGGGACUGUGAAACAGAUGCAGAGGAGGGCACCUCCCUAACAGCCUCAGUAGUUGCAGAUGUAAGAAAGAGCCAGCUUCCAGCAGAAGGGGAUGCUGGGGCAGAGUGGGCUGCAGCUGUUCUUAAGCAGGAGAGAGCUCAUGAGGUGGGGGCCCAGGGUGGGCCACCUGUGGCACAAGUGGAGCAGGACCUCCCUAUCUCAAGAGAGAACCUCACAGAUCUGGUGGUGGACACAGACACUCUAGGGGAAUCCACCCAGCCACAGAGAGAGGGAGCCCAGGUCCCCACAGGAAGGGAGAGAGAACAACAUGUGGGUGGGACCAAGGACUCUGAAGACAACUAUGGUGAUUCUGAAGAUCUGGACCUACAAGCUACCCAGUGCUUUCUGGAGAAUCAGGGCCUGGAAGCAGUCCAGAGCAUGGAGGAUGAACCUACCCAGGCCUUCAUGUUGACUCCACCCCAAGAGCUUGGCCCUUCCCAUUGCAGCUUCCAGACAACAGGUACCCUAGAUGAACCAUGGGAGGUCCUGGCUACACAGCCAUUCUGUCUGAGAGAGUCUGAGGACUCUGAGACCCAGCCUUUUGACACGCACCUUGAGGCCUAUGGACCUUGCCUGUCUCCACCUAGGGCAAUACCAGGAGACCAACAUCCAGAGAGCCCAGUUCACACAGAGCCAAUGGGGAUUCAAGGCAGAGGGAGGCAGACUGUGGAUAAAGUCAUGGGUAUACCAAAAGAAACAGCAGAGAGGGUGGGCCCUGAGAGAGGGCCAUUGGAGAGAGAAACUGAGAAACUGCUACCAGAAAGACAGACAGAUGUGACAGGAGAGGAAGAAUUAACCAAGGGGAAACAGGACAGAGAACAAAAACAGUUGUUAGCUAGAGACACCCAGAGACAAGAAUCUGACAAAAAUGGGGAAAGUGCAAGUCCUGAAAGAGAUAGGGAGAGUUUGAAGGUAGAAAUUGAGACAUCUGAGGAAAUACAAGAGAAACAAGUACAGAAGCAGACCCUUCCAAGCAAAGCAUUUGAGAGAGAAGUAGAGAGACCAGUAGCAAACAGAGAGUGCGAUCCAGCCGAGUUAGAAGAGAAGGUGCCCAAAGUGAUCCUGGAGAGAGAUACACAGAGAGGGGAGCCAGAGGGAGGGAGCCAGGACCAGAAAGGGCAGGCCUCCAGCCCAACACCAGAGCCUGGGGUGGGGGCGGGGGACCUUCCGGGACCUACCUCAGCCCCCGUACCUUCUGGGAGCCAGUCAGGUGGAAGGGGAUCCCCAGUGAGCCCCAGGAGGCAUCAGAAAGGCCUCCUGAAUUGCAAGAUGCCACCUGCUGAGAAGGCUUCCAGGAUCAGAGCUGCUGAGAAGGUUUCCAGGGGCGAUCAGGAAUCUCCAGAUGCUUGUCUGCCUCCUACAGUACCUGAAGCCCCAGCCCCACCCCAAAAGCCCCUUAACUCUCAGAGCCAGAAACAUCUUGCACCUCCGCCCCUUCUUUCUCCCCUUUUACCUUCUAUCAAGCCAACCGUUCGUAAGACCAGGCAAGAUGGGAGUCAGGAAGCUCCAGAGGCUCCCUUGUCCUCAGAGCUGGAGCCUUUCCACCCAAAGCCUAAAAUUAGAACUCGGAAGUCCUCCAGAAUGACACCCUUUCCAGCUACCUCUGCUGCCCCUGAGCCCCACCCUUCCACCUCCACAGCCCAGCCAGUCACUCCCAAGCCCACAUCUCAGGCCACUAGGAGCAGGACAAAUAGGUCCUCUGUCAAGACCCCUGAACCAGUUGUCCCCACAGCCCCUGAGCUCCAGCCUUCCACCUCCACAGACCAGCCUGUCACCUCUGAGCCCACAUCUCAGGUUACUAGGGGAAGAAAAAGUAGAUCCUCUGUCAAGACCCCUGAAACAGUUGUGCCCACAGCCCUUGAGCUCCAGCCUUCCACCUCCACCGACCGACCUGUCACCUCUGAACCCACCUCUCAGGCUACUAGGGGAAGAAAAAAUAGAUCCUCUGUCAAGACCCCUGAACCAGUUGUCCCCACAGCCCCUGAGCUCCAGCCUUCCACCUCCACAGACCAGCCUGUCACUUCUGAGCCCACAUAUCAGGCUACUAGGGGAAGAAAAAAUAGAUCCUCUGUCAAGACCCCUGAACCAGUUGUGCCCACAGCCCCUGAGCUCCGGCCUUCCACCUCCACAGACCGACCUGUCACCCCCAAGCCCACAUCUCGGACCACUAGGAGCAGGACAAAUAUGUCCUCUGUCAAGACCCCUGAAACAGUUGUCCCCACAGCCCCUGAGCUCCAGAUUUCCACCUCCACAGACCAACCUGUCACCCCUAAGCCCACAUCUCGGACCACUAGGAGCAGGACAAAUAUGUCCUCUGUGAAGAACCCUGAAUCAACUGUCCCUAUAGCCCCUGAGCUCCCACCUUCCACCUCCACAGAGCAGCCUGUCACCCCUGAGCCCACAUCUCGGGCUACUAGGGGAAGAAAAAAUAGAUCCUCUGGCAAGACCCCUGAAACACUUGUCCCCACAGCCCCUAAGCUCGAGCCUUCCACUUCCACAGACCAACCUGUCACUCCUGAGCCCACAUCUCAGGCCACCAGGGGCAGGACAAAUAGGUCCUCUGUGAAGACCCCUGAAACAGUUGUCCCCACAGCCCCUGAGCUCCAGCCUUCCACCUCCACAGACCAGCCUGUUACCCCUGAGCCUACGUCUCAGGCUACUAGGGGAAGAACAGAUAGAUCCUCUGUCAAGACUCCUGAAACAGUUGUCCCCACAGCCCCUGAGCUACAGGCUUCCGCCUCCACAGACCAGCCUGUCACCUCUGAGCCCACAUCUCGGACCACUAGGGGAAGAAAAAAUCGGUCCUCUGUCAAGACCCCUGAAACAGUUGUGCCCGCAGCCCCUGAGCUCCAGCCUUCCACCUCCACAGACCAACCUGUCACCCCUGAGCCCACAUCUCGGGCCACUAGGGGCAGGACAAAUAGGUCCUCUGUCAAGACCCCUGAAUCAAUUGUCCCUAUAGCCCCUGAGCUUCAGCCUUCCACCUCCAGAAACCAGCUUGUCACCCCUGAGCCCACAUCUCGGGCCACUAGGUGCAGGACAAAUAGGUCCUCUGUCAAGACCCCUGAGCCAGUUGUCCCCACAGCCCCUGAGCCCCAUCCUACCACCUCCACAGACCAGCCUGUCACCCCCAAGCUCACAUCUAGGGCCACUAGGAGAAAGACAAAUAGGUCCUCUGUCAAGACUCCCAAACCAGUUGAACCAGCAGCCUCUGAUCUUGAGCCUUUUACCCCCACAGACCAGUCCGUCACCCCUGAGGCCAUAGCUCAGGGUGGUCAGAGCAAAACACUGAGGUCUUCCACAGUAAGAGCUAUGCCGGUUCCUACCACCCCUGAAUUCCAAUCUCCUGUCACCACAGACCAGCCUAUUUCCCCUGAGCCUAUUACUCAACCCAGUUGCAUCAAGAGGCAGAGAGCCGCUGGGAACCCUGGCUCCCUCGCAGCUCCCAUUGACCAUAAGCCUUGCUCUGCACCCUUGGAACCUAAAUCCCAGGCCUCAAGGAACCAAAGAUGGGGAGCAGUGAGAGCAGCUGAAUCCCUUACAGCCAUUCCUGAGCCUGCCUCUCCCCAGCUUCUUGAGACACCAAUUCAUGCCUCCCAGAUCCAAAAGGUGGAACCAGCAGGUAGAUCUAGGUUCACCCCGGAGCUCCAGCCUAAGGCCUCUCAAAGCCGCAAGAGGUCUUUAGCUACCAUGGAUUCACCACCACAUCAAAAACAGCCCCAAAGAGGGGAAGUCUCCCAGAAGACAGUGAUUAUCAAGGAAGAGGAAGAAGAUACUGCAGAGAAGCCAGGGAAGGAAGAGGAUGUCGUGACUCCAAAACCAGGCAAGAGAAAGAGAGACCAGGCAGAGGAGGAGCCCAACAGAAUACCAAGCCGCAGCCUCCGACGGACCAAACUUAACCAAGAAUCAACAGCCCCCAAAGUGCUCUUCACAGGAGUGGUGGAUGCUCGGGGAGAGCGGGCUGUGCUGGCACUGGGGGGAAGUCUGGCUGGUUCAGCGGCAGAGGCUUCCCACCUGGUCACUGAUCGCAUCCGCCGGACAGUCAAGUUCCUGUGUGCCCUGGGGCGGGGAAUCCCCAUUCUGUCCCUGGACUGGCUGCAUCAGUCCCGCAAGGCUGGUUUCUUCUUACCCCCGGAUGAAUAUGUGGUGACCGACCCUGAGCAAGAGAAGAACUUUGGCUUUAGCCUUCAAGACGCACUGAGCAGGGCUCGGGAGCGAAGGCUGCUAGAGGGCUAUGAGAUCUAUGUGACCCCUGGAGUCCAGCCACCACCACCUCAGAUGGGAGAGAUUAUUAGCUGCUGUGGAGGCACAUACCUACCCAGCAUGCCUCGGUCCUAUAAGCCUCAGAGAGUUGUGAUCACAUGCCCUCAGGACUUCCCUCAUUGCUCCAUUCCACUACGGGUUGGGCUGCCCCUCCUCUCGCCUGAGUUCCUGCUGACUGGAGUGCUGAAGCAGGAAGCCAAGCCAGAGGCCUUUGUCCUCUCCCCUUUGGAGAUGUCAUCCACCUGAGAACUCCACUACCCUUUUCCCUCCCAGACCACGAAUUAGAAGAUAUGUGGAAGAAAGAACUCAGGGCGUUAGAAAGGAUUGGGGUAUAUUGAUACAACUUGUCCUGGAACAUGGGUGGGACCAGAAAUCUUUAUGAAUAAAUGAAAAGAUAAGGGAUUUGGAAGCCACAGGUUGUUUUUUGUUUGUUUGUUUGUUUUUUUAAUGGCCAUUUUAUUUUAUUUGUAUUUAUAGUUUUUUAUUUGUAUAGAUUUAGGGGAUACAAGAUUUCUUACAUGCAUGUAUUAAAUGGCCAUUUUAAAAUUAGCUAGUUUCAUGCUCAGAUGUCAUAAGUGGCAGCUAUCUUUAGCCAGACUGUUGCAGUUAUUGCUCGAUGCCACUCAUGGUGUCCUACCUCCUAUUUGGAAACCAUCUCUAUUUUUUUCUUACUGAGAUUCUUACUUUGGGGUCAGGAACUUGAAGGGAUGCUUGGAGUGAGUAGAUUUGAGGGUCCAGUUAUGGAGUGCUACUAAAACAUUUUCUUCUCUCCUGGCCUCUGGAAGCAUCUUUAGCUUUGACUUUGGGCAAGUCUCUGUACUUUUCUGGCCAGCUUUUCCAGGAUUUAUAAAAUUAGAGCUUCGGCUUGACCUCUGUGAUAAAUAAAUAUUCACUCUGUGCCUUA